AGUGUGGAAUUGCUUCUUUUCUUUGGUCAAACACUAACUUUGGCAGAGGAUAGACACAGCUUAGGAAGACUGAAUUUUAAGUCUUCUGAAUUGUUUUUCUGGACUUCCAAAUCUCAAGUGAUAAGACCAGCAGAAGCAGGAGGAGGGAGGAACAGAAGAAAUAUUUGAAGAGAUCAUGGCUGAAAAAAUUUUCCAAAUUUGAUGAAACCUAUAAACCCAAAGAUCCAAGAUGCUCAGUGAACCCCAAACAAAAGCUAUAUGAGGAAAACUACAUCAAAGCAUAAUUGUUUUGUUUAAAUCCACUGAUAAGGAUAAAAUUCUAAAAGAACCCAAAGAAAAAAUACACAUUACAUAGGAAGAAAGUUUGAAAGCUCGUGGAAUCUCUAGACCAGAAAUUAAACUUCUUGAUGCCCUUCGCAGUGCUUAGCAUAUGACUGAGUGCACAGGCAGUUCUUAGUUGGCUGUAUUUGAUAGGAAUGCAUUGAAGCUGUGGUUAUGGCCUAUGAUGGGCAUCAGAUAAGAGCCAAAUACUGGAUGGAGAAAGGUCGAGCAGAAAUGUACCUCCUGAAGUAGCCCUGGGAAGGCCAGCGUUGGAUUGUGUAGGUUGCAAAAUGCAGUACCUCAGACUUGCAACUCUGAAAAGCACUGUUUGAAAUCUCUGUAAAGAGUGAAAAACUUCAAGUUUUAACCAAUGAGUGUUUUAGAGGUUAAAGUUUAAACUCUGACUUGGAAGCACGCUGGGUAGGACUCCUCUGCUCACUCAGACUCAAGUUGGAUCAUCAGAAUCUCUCUUGUGUUGCUGUGAAUGAUUUGCAUUGAAAUUCCCAGCUAGAACUGGAGGAAAGAGGAUUACAAACCAGGAGAUAUAAAGACCUGAAGAUAGUCUUUUCUGUCCAAAGAUGGAAAACAGUACUACUACCAUUUCUCGGGAGGAGCUUGAAGAACUACAAGAGGCAUUUAAUAAAAUAGAUAUUGACAAUAGUGGGUAUGUCAGUGACUAUGAACUUCAAGACCUGUUUAAGGAAGCAAGCCUUCCUCUGCCUGGCUACAAGGUGCGCGAGAUUGUGGAGAAAAUUCUAUCAGUUGCUGACAGCAACAAAGAUGGCAAAAUCAGUUUUGAAGAGUUUGUGUCACUAAUGCAAGAAUUAAAAAGCAAAGAUAUCAGCAAAACAUUCCGAAAAAUAAUUAACAAGAGGGAAGGGAUUACUGCUAUUGGAGGAACUUCAACUAUUUCCAGUGAGGGCACACAGCAUUCUUAUUCAGAGGAAGAAAAAGUGGCUUUUGUUAACUGGAUAAACAAAGCCCUGGAGAAUGACCCUGACUGUAAGCAUCUUAUACCCAUGAAUCCCAAUGAUGAUAGUCUUUUCAAGUCACUUGCAGAUGGCAUCCUUCUUUGCAAAAUGAUCAACUUAUCUGAACCAGAUACAAUUGAUGAAAGAGCCAUCAAUAAGAAAAAGCUCACGCCAUUCACUAUUUCUGAAAAUUUAAACCUAGCUCUGAAUUCUGCCUCAGCCAUUGGUUGUACAGUGGUCAACAUUGGUGCAUCAGAUCUCAAAGAAGGAAAACCUCACUUGGUCUUGGGACUUCUCUGGCAGAUCAUCAAAGUUGGCCUUUUUGCUGAUAUUGAGAUUUCCAGGAAUGAAGCUCUGAUUGCAUUGUUAAAUGAAGGUGAGGAACUAGAGGAGCUGAUGAAGCUUUCUCCCGAGGAAUUACUGCUGCGAUGGGUGAACUACCAUCUGACCAAUGCAGGAUGGCAUACCAUCAGCAACUUCAGCCAAGACAUUAAGGACUCGAGAGCCUAUUUUCAUCUGCUUAAUCAGAUUGCCCCUAAAGGUGGGGAAGAUGGACCUGCCAUUGCCAUUGACCUUUCAGGAAUUAAUGAGACAAAUGACCUGAAGCGUGCUGGACUCAUGCUUCAAGAAGCAGAUAAACUGGGCUGCAAACAGUUUGUUACUCCUGCAGAUGUGGUUUCAGGCAAUCCUAAACUUAAUUUAGCUUUUGUAGCUAAUUUGUUUAACACAUACCCGUGCCUGCACAAGCCGAAUAAUAAUGACAUCGAUAUGAAUUUACUGGAAGGAGAGAGCAAGGAAGAGAGAACAUUUCGGAACUGGAUGAAUUCCUUGGGAGUCAACCCAUACAUUAAUCAUUUGUACAGUGACCUUGCAGAUGCUUUAGUGAUCUUUCAGCUCUAUGAGAUGAUCCGAGUGCCAGUCAACUGGAGCCAUGUCAACAAACCUCCUUAUCCUGCCCUUGGAGGGAACAUGAAGAAGAUUGAAAACUGUAACUAUGCAGUGGAACUUGGGAAGAACAAGGCCAAAUUCUCCUUGGUUGGCAUUGCUGGGCAGGACCUAAAUGAAGGGAAUUCAACACUUACCCUGGCAUUGGUAUGGCAGCUGAUGAGAAGGUACACAUUGAAUGUGUUAUCGGAUCUUGGAGAGGGUGAAAAAGUAAAUGAUGAAAUUAUAAUUAAAUGGGUCAAUCAGACUCUUAAAAGUGCAAACAAAAAGACUUCUAUUUCCAGCUUCAAGGAUAAAUCUAUAAGCACAAGUUUACCUGUCCUAGAUUUAAUAGAUGCCAUUGCACCAAAUGCAGUUCGUCAAGAAAUGAUCAGGAGAGAAAACUUAUCUGAUGAGGACAAGCUGAACAAUGCUAAAUACGCCAUUUCAGUUGCUCGAAAGAUCGGUGCCCGGAUAUAUGCAUUACCUGAUGACCUCGUAGAAGUGAAACCAAAGAUGGUUAUGACGGUGUUUGCAUGCUUAAUGGGAAAAGGACUGAACAGAAUAAAAUAAUCAUUUCAUAUGAUUUUCUGCCACAUUAAACAUAUUGUAUGCCUCACAGUUUACAGGAUUCUGAAAUGUAGUGGGUGUAAAACCAGAGAUUAUUUGUAUGCUCAAAAUAGUUAUAUAUUCAUUAAUGAAUUCAAUAUCCUGUUCAUACUAGUUAGAGCUGGUCAGCCUUUUUGGGUAACACAGUUAAUUUACCAACUGAUACAGAUAAUAGAAUAUAUUCAUAAUCAAGCUGAUACUUCAUGAUUAAAUUAUUUUUGUUGCUUAAAAGUCGUAUUAGACAAGACUAAAUCAUUCUUUUUUAUGGUUCAAAAAAGAUGAAUACAAACGUUUUUGCAGGUUCUGCUGUGAAAUGUGGUUUGAUUUUUUUGGUGUGUUAAUUUUGAUCAUAAAUGCAUUCAUACUCAUAAUCCAGUUUAAUCCUUUUAUUUGCUUCCUCCAACUAUUUAAAGUGGUCCAAAAACACUUUUCUGUAAGUUUCUAUACUGUCUAAAACCUUAUGGUGACCAGAAUUGUUUAUUAAUAUCAAACUUUUUUAUAUAUGAGAACUAAUUCUUGAAUAAACCCCAAAGUUCACUCUCUUGUUUAAGUAGCAGCAGCUUUUUACUUAAAAUUUAAUUUUAACUACAUUGAUACUUUACACAUCCUAGUUUGGUAACACAGCUUUAACUAUGUCAUGCAACAUAUAUAUGUUGGUAGGAUGUUAUUAGAGAGAUAUGUGUGCAUAUAUAUUUUUUUGCACCUGAAUCACCCAGCUUUUCAUAAGUGGUAUGUUUAAUUGGUCAUUCAGCCAACCAUCAGUAUUUUCCCCCCACAACAUGUGUAACACUUUUCAGUCUGUGGAUAUCUGAUACAUUAAGAUUUCUUUUUAUAAGUAUUCAUUUUGAAUGUGCAUAUAGUUAUUUGACCCCUUCCAAAUACUUGUAGCCAAACAUUGGCUAGAACAUCCCAAGAUAUGCUGACACUGUCCUGUUAGCUUCAUAUUAUACUUGCUAGUUUAGGUCUCUAUAGAAGCCCUAUAUAAUUUAGAAUAUGCCCACUGAAUAUCUUUAAUAGAAAGUAACAUAAAGCUAGUAUUCAAUGUAGAGUAUUUUCAUAUGUUUUUCACAGCCCGUUACAAAUUGGCAAUGUUUGGUUAAUGUUUGUAUUACUUGGAAAUCGCUACAGCUUGGACUAUUUUUUUCUAAAUUUUUAGCAUUAGUCCAUUUCUGCUGCUAACAAUUGAAUCCAGAAAUCUACUUUCUCCAUCUUCCACUGUUAGUGCCAGUGAGCAAUACUGUUGUGCAACAAAAAUGUCACUUUAUCUCAGUGUGAAUGAGUAGUCUAAAUUCCCUUUCUACCAUUGAUUUAAAUAUAUAUAUUGGUAAGAGAGACUGCCCAUGUGUUUAGAAUAGAAUUUUUUAAAUGAAAUGAUCAACAGGUGGAAUUUGAAAUAUAUUCUUCUACAAAAGAGAUUUCUUUCCCUUUUAUAUUUUGAUGAUUGUUUUCUUAAGAUUAAGAUAUGUUCUUGCUCUUUUAUAAGAUUAUUUAAAUUAUGUUUCCCUCUGAUUUUUUUUCACCAUUGUAUUUACUAAGUUAUUGGAUUUACAUGAAAUCUGGCACUUUAGGGUGUUCUUUUUCUCACAGAGUAUAUUUAAUAAAAAUGCUGUGUAUAUAGAAA